GGAGCUCUAGGCCGGCAUCUCUCCGCGAGCCGCGGGUCAAGUGCCGGCGGCUAAUGGUGCGCGAGGAGCCGCCACCCAUUCGGCGUUGGCUCUGGCGUCGGGGUCGUUGUGACAACCGCUCCAGUAGCCGUUUCCGAGGCAGCAGGUGCGGCCGCUUUAGCCCUGAGCGGGCUCUGCGGCUGCCUGCGAGUCUCUGCUGUGCCGACCCUUCUCUUCGCGGACCCCACGCCAAGCAGCGACCCUGAGGCGACAGCCGGAGCGCCCGGCAAUGGCGGCCUCGACGGCCUCCCACCGGCCCAUCAAGGGGAUCUUGAAGAACAAGACCUCUACGACUUCCUCUAUGGUGGCGUCGGCCGAACAGCCCCGCAGGAGUGUCGACGAGGAGCUGAGCAAAAAAUCCCAGAAGUGGGAUGAAAUUAACAUCUUGGCGACCUAUCAUCCAGCAGACAAAGGCUAUGGUUUAAUGAAAAUAGAUGAACCAAGCCCUCCUUACCAUAGUAUGAUGGGUGAUGAUGAAGAUGCGUGUAGGGACACCGAGACCACUGAAGCCAUGGCGCCAGACAUCCUAGCCAAGAAAUUAGCUGCUGCUGAAGGCUUGGAGCCAAAGUACCGGAUUCAGGAACAAGAAAGCAGUGGAGAGGAGGAUAGUGACCUCUCACCUGAAGAACGAGAAAAAAAGCGACAAUUUGAAAUGAGAAGGAAGCUUCACUACAAUGAAGGACUCAAUAUCAAACUAGCCAGACAAUUAAUUUCAAAAGACCUACAUGAUGAUGAUGAAGAUGAAGAAAUGUUAGAGACUGCAGAUGGAGAAAGCAUGAAUACGGAAGAAUCAAAUCAAGGAUCUACUCCAAGUGACCAACAGCAAAACAAAUUACGAAGUUCAUAGAAGAGAUUUGUUCAACACUGCAAUUGUUUGUUAGAUAUAAACCCUGUGACUAUAAUACAUUGCUUCUUGUUCUCCACAAUUCAUGACUUAAGUACCAAAAUGCAUACCAGUUAUUAUAUAUUGCCAAGAAUUAAAUGAUAAACUUAGAGACUAAUUAGACUGAAAAUGCCUAAUUGAUAUAUAUAUUCUUAUGCCUAGUACUUUACCACAAAUACAGUGUAAUAUCAUCAGUCCAAAACUGCAUUACUUUCAUAAGAACACUGGUUAAUUUGUAUAAGAUAUUAUAGAGCUUUUUAUGCUUUAGAAGUUAAGCAAUAUCUUUGGGGGGGAACUAAUUUAUUUUCAUCACUCGAAAUGUGGUAGCUCUUACAAAGUUUGUUGAUUUGUUUUUUUAAAAAUCAAAAGCCAGUUGAACAACAGGAUAUAUAGACUUAUAAAUAUUCAAGCUGAAUCGUAUUUUAACACUUCUCUUCAACUUGAUUUGUCUGUUUAAUUGAAAAGAAUUGUAAGAGUUACUGUUGCAUUUUCUGACCUACUACCUUUAAAAUUCCUGUUGAGUUUCUUUGUGUUUACAAGGAAAGGACUGAACUUUUUCUCAUCAAAACUAGCUUUUUUCCCCACAAAUAAAUUAUCAGGUUAAACUUUCACCAAUGUCUGCUCUGUUUUUUGGCAGGGGGUUUGUUUGUUUUUGUUUUUUAAUGUUUUUGGUACACUGGGCAGACUUCAGAGCAGUUUUUUAAAAAAUAAAUAUUCUAAUGUAGCUAUCUCGCCAUUCCCUUUAAAUACCUGUCUUAACCUCCUGCUUUUAUUUCCUACUCCUUUCCACACAUACACACACAAUCUUUUACCUUUUAAAGGAUCAUUAAGAUUGUCACGACAUUAGGAACUCUUUCUGUCACUCUUCUGUCAUUUGCUGCUGUGUGGAAAUUCUUAUUUUGACCAUCAAUGCCUAUGAAUUCUUCUAAUACAUGAAGAAAAUAGAUUGAGUAGCAGCAGUACUAUAGGCAGGAAAUACAGUUUAACUGCUGAAUUUCUAUGCCUCUCGAUUUACAGAUUGCUAAUUAAAUUGCUAUUAUUAGUUUGGCUUAAUUAGACUUAAGAAAACAACCGAGGGUUUUUUUUUGUUUUUUGAGGGUUUUCUUUGCAUGAGAAUUGUAUGUAACCAGUGAUAUGAUUAUUCCUGAAUGUACAGACAGAAGUAAGCCUGGACAUUUUUUAAUUUAAAAACUUUAAAUAGUCCCUGCUUUAAGGGAAUAUGAUAAUGUAUACUAUGACAAAUGUACUUUAUUCCUCUAACGCAGUAAGAAUUAUGUGGAAUAUUUUCCUUAAACGAAGUGCAGGAAAGCCC